GCUUGCUGUGACUGGUGGAGCUGCCGCGCUGUCCGCGUUAUCUCCUCCCGGUGAGAACGAACCGCAGUGUCCACCGGCGAGGAGCCAGCCCUGUCCCGGUCAGAGAAAGACGACGAGGAUACCUGGGAGCGGGCGGCGGCCGGGCUGGGCCGCGCCGGUGCGGGCUGGCGACUCUGCUCCUCCGCUUGCUGCUGUCUCUGGGAACUGGGUGCCAGCGCUGAGGGGCUUCCAGCGGACAGGGACCCCCUUCCCCGGCUCCCCUGCCCACCCUGCCGGGGAGGGCGGAAGAUGCCGGUGAAGAAGAAGAGAAAAUCCCCUGGGGUGGCAGCAGCAGUAGCGGAAGACGGAGGCCUCAAAAAGUGUAAAAUCUCCAGGUACCAUCUCCCCCCACCCUUCAAGCUUCCCUCCUCCCUCCUUUGCUGGACAACUGGAGGAAAAGGAGUCGGGCCCGGCCUGCCGGGCUGGGGCUGGAGACAGCUAUUGCAGAUCCCAACCCCCUGCUAGACUAAUAAGUGGAGAGGAACAUUUUUCAAGCAAGAAGUGCCUGGCUUGGUUUUAUGAAUAUGCAGGUCCUGAUGAAGUUGUAGGGCCAGAAGGAAUGGAAAAAUUUUGUGAAGACAUUGGUGUUGAACCUGAAAAUAUUAUUAUGUUAGUUUUAGCGUGGAAAUUGGAGGCUGAAAGCAUGGGAUUUUUUACCAAGGAAGAAUGGUUAAAGGGAAUGACUUCAUUACAGUGUGACUGCACAGAAAAGUUACAAAACAAAUUUGACUUUUUGCGCUCACAGUUGAAUGAUAUUUCGUCAUUUAAGAAUAUCUACAGAUAUGCCUUUGAUUUUGCAAGGGAUAAAGAUCAGAGAAGCCUUGAUAUUGAUACUGCUAAAUCUAUGUUAGCUCUUCUGCUUGGGAGGACAUGGCCACUGUUUUCAGUAUUUUACCAGUACCUGGAGCAAUCAAAGUAUCGUGUUAUGAACAAAGAUCAAUGGUACAAUGUAUUAGAAUUCAGCAGAACAGUCCAUGCUGAUCUUAGUAACUAUGAUGAAGAUGGUGCUUGGCCUGUUCUUCUUGAUGAAUUUGUUGAGUGGCAAAAAGUCCGUCAGACAUCAUAGCAAGAACUAUGUGAAGAAAAUGCAAACCUUUCAAUUCCCACGUGUAUACAAGCUAAUGUGAUGAGGGGGAAAAAAAUCCAACGGGUGCAUUUUCAUUCAUAUGAAAGACUUCUCAUAGUACUUUUUUUUCCUUUUUUUAAAGGAGGUUUUUCUUGUUACAUGUGAUGGGCAUUGAGCCACACCUCUUCUUAGACUGAAUAUUGAAGUUUUUGUUUUGAGUUAUGUUUAUAACAUUUAUUUCAGAACAAUAAAGAUUCAGAUUUGUGACAAAGGCCUUAAAGUGAAGAUGUCCCUUGAGUGUCAGAGUGGUAUUUAUUUUUGUAAAUUUGAAUUUUUUGAUUUUUGAGGUUCCAAUUCACCGUGAAUUUACAGAAUUUUCAAGAUUUUAAACAGUCUUAAUAUUUGGCAACAUAGUCUGCUGAUGGUAUGGCUCAUUAUAGUCAUCUCUGCACAAUUUGGAAGACUGUUGGCCUUGACUUCUGGGAUAAUGAUUUGCUGAUGCAGCUAAUAAACAUUUCUAGGUAUUGGAAAAAUGCUCCUACUUUUAGCUCUGGGUUUCUAUAAAAGCUGCCAAGGUCUUAUGCAGAUGUCUUAUCUCAGAGAGCUUAGAAUUGGAAAGAUUAUGUCCAGUUGUUUUGUUUUCUAAAAAAGUUGUAUUAUUAAGUUGUAUCAUCAUUAUUAUUGUUGAUAAUAGCAUAUUUAUAUUUUUAACUGUCAUUAUAUAGGGAAUUUUGUUUAAAGCACUUUUUUUUUUUUUUUUUGCCUUAAGAGAACGUUAGCUGUGAUAUGGAUUUAAUUAAGAUACACAUAGGAAAAGAAGACAAUAGAAUAAGGAAUCAUGAGAGAACUCUGGGUAUAAUUAAUUGUGCACAACUCAAUAGAGCCAUUUACGUUGGUAGUAUUGCAGCUUGCUAAUUAUCACAAUUUUCUGCCUGUUGGUAAUCAAGUGUCUUGAGGAAAGGGAAGGCUUUCCUAAUUCAUGUAAAAGGCACUUUUGUACUAGCAGCAGGCCUGUUUGUACAUUCCUUUUCAAACCAUCCAGUAUCCCAGUGAUAUGAAAACUUUGUUCAUAUUCAUAGCCCAGUCACAACUUCAGAAACAUUUCUAGUGUCAUUGUUUGAGUAGAGAGAAGUAAAGAGGUUAUUUUUCCAUAAUAAGGGAGUGUUUCUAUUAGGAUUUAAGGUAAAGGUUGAUUUUUCAGUGGUGAAUUUGUUUAAAGAAUGAUUUCUCCAUAUUGAUUACCUAAGAGAAUGACAUUUUAAAGUGUUUUAUUGUUUGCUUUUUAGUUAAUCAGCUGGGAAAAAAAUGAUUGCCACUGUUUUACUUGCCUUCUUAAUAAGAUUACUUUGUACAGUUUUCUGAAACACCCAUAAUAGUGGGAGACAGUUUUCCUAAAUGUCUUAUAGAAAAGGAUAAUACAGAAUGCUCCUCUUAAGUAUUAGAAUCACUGAGUUAUGAACUGAGCAUACCAGUGGUGUUAGGAUUUAAUAUUAUGAAUGAUGUUUUAAUAUCAAAUUUAUUAUAAGGAAAGCAUUUAGAUUUGUAGACCUUUAAAUUUAUAAUUUAGUUGACUCUUCAAGGCACAUCUGAACUGAAGAACAUAUCCACUUUUGUUAAAUUCCAAAACAUAUAAGCAAAAUCUUAUAAAUUGUCCAUUUGUAACCUGAACUAAUGGUAAUAUCUUUUUCAUCUUCAGUAUUUGAGUAAAAUAGGGAACACUUAAAGCUUAUAGAUGACAUGUUUUUUAAAAGGUAUAUUUAUGAAAGCACAGGCAUCCUUGGUAUACGCAGGAGAUUGAUACCAGGACCCUUGUGUAUACCCAAAUCUGUGCAUACUUAAGUCCUACAGUCAUCCCUGUGGAACCUGCCUGUAUAAAAAGUCAGCCCUCCCCGUGUAUGUAGGUGUCGCAUCCCGGGAAUACUGUAUUUUCAAUCCAUGUUUGGUUUAAAAAAAUCUGCGUAUAAGCAGACCCACACAGUUCAAACUCAUGCUGUUCAAGGGUCAACAGUAUUUACUUUGCAUACUUAUCCAAAGAUACCUUUAAGACUUUUUGAGUCUGAAAAUGAAAUUUACUUUAUUUUUUCCCUUAAAGUCAACUGUCCUAUCCUACCCUAGCCAUACUUUGGAGUCCAGUACCACUGAGGCCACGCUUGCUUUACUCUAUUGCUCCAUCUAUUUCUCUUACCUUCUUAAAGUUAUAACAUUUGCCUACUUUGAAGGCAAAUUUACUCUGCCUAAUUCAUCAGUCAGGGUGUGGGCUGUGUCCCUUCCUGUCUUUCCUUUGUUAAUUUUGAAUAGCAUUUAAUUUACUGGGAAAUUUAUGAUCAAAAAUGUUAAGUGAUAUAAACAAUACAAUAUUAAGGACCCUGCAGUAUAAAAAAGUCUAACUGUUGUGGUUCCUUUUUUGACUAGUUAGCUUUAAGUGCCUUCCCACGAACCCUGUUGUAAAAUUUUCAGAACUACUUCCCUUUGUACAGGAUGAAAUACCGUAUGGUGCUUUAUAACAUGGAGUUGAGUUGUUUCUAUAAGAAUAUUAUACAAAUGUAAUACUACUGGGAGAAAGUAGAGCCAGAUGUUGAUUGGACAGAUUGCAACCCCCCCACCCCCCCACUCCUCGGGGCCAAUAAUUCUUAAUAAGGUAUGAUGUUAAUACCUCUAGGAAAUUGCCAGGGAUUCAGGUGACAGUGUGUGAUGAAAACGGUGUAUUGUGUGCUGGCCUGACUGCAUUACCAUGUUUGUCUUCUAUUGUCUAAUGAUUUCUUAUUUCUUAAAUGCUGCUGAUAAAAUUAUUGAUAUAAUACAUUUUUGACAGUAGUAGCAUUUUUGUGUAUAAUGUAUAGAUUUUAUUGGUUUUUACUCAGAAGCACUCUAGAUUAGUGUUUCUUGAACUGCAAUUUGAAGCCUUCUUUGGGAAUGUUAGAUUGAGGAGUAUUUCUCUUAAAUACAAAUGCCUUUUCAUCUAGCAAACCAAAAAUUAUAUCUUAAUAUUGAAUGCCAUCACUCGGGGUCGGGGUGGGAGUAAAUUCUGAGAUAACUCCAGAGUUUUCAAGGCAUACAAGGUAUGUGGAAUAGCACAGAUUCAGAAUACAUGAUACAUACGUAUAAAAUGAAACAUUUCACUUUGAAGUAUUUCUUCAACAAAACAUGUCCUGUCUGCCUACUUGCUAAUGUGAAAUUAUGAAAGGAUUUAUUGAAAUAUAUGUUCAGUUUGAGGUGUAAUUGGUAAGAAUGCCAGGUGUUGUUCUUCUGCCCUCUUAAAGAAGUGUACUUAAAACUAUUGUGAUAAUUCAUCUCUGAUAAAACUUUGUUCUGGCCUUCAAGGCUCUUACAGCUUAAUGUUUUAAAUGUCUAAGGCAUCAAAUAAAUUGAGGGCAUUUUAAUAAAAAAAAAAAAGGAAAACUAAAUGCCUUUCUUUGUUAAAGCAAAAGGCCAAAAAUAAAAAAUAAAAUUAAAACCCCCCCCAAAAAAACCCAAAAGUCUUACUCCUAAAGAAGAAUUCUUACCUCUAAGGAGGAAUCCUUCCCUCUUGAGGAAAUACCACUUUUUGAGUGACAUUAGAAAUCAUCACAAGGAAACAUUUCAAAGAAAGGAUCAUUUUUUUUUCAGGAGAAAGAGGAAUAACAAUUUCAUUAACUUCCUCAAUAGGAAAGGCUAGUCUGAAUUAUUAAAUAUUCUGGAUUAUAUCUUUUUUUAAUGAUAUAGUUUUAUUACUUCAGGAAUAUUUGGUAAGAACCAGGUAAACCUAUUGUUUAAGAUUUGUUCUUUUUUGUUAAUAGACCUAUGAUUAGUAUGGUGGAAGCCCAAAAAGCAGUCUAAUUUUUAUGAUAAACUUACAGACUGUGGAAAGAUGAAUUUCUGCCCCAAACCUUGGAUAAGUUGUCAUUAAUUUAAUUGUAGAGAUUUUUCUAGUGAACUUGUACUUCACUGGAACAAAUCUUUAGAUCUUUUAAAGCACAAUUUAUUUAUGUUUUUAAAAACAGUCUUAAAACUGAUCGAUCAUACAUUUGCUGUGUCCACCUUACAAUCUUUUACAUUCUAUUAGUACAGAUAGUGUUUCCUUUGCUCCUUUUCCUGACCAGUUGUUAUUGGUGUGACCAUUUUCUUUUUAGGAUCGAUGAAACAUUUUGCUGUGUAUGCUGUGUCAUGUAUUAGAACCUCUUAUAAUAUGGCUCAUUUUUACAUGGUUUCUGAUUUACCAUGUGUUAAAUAUUCCUUAAAAUACAUCUAGUAACACUAUAUAGUAAGGUUAGAUUUUAACCUAAGUAUUGAAUCUUGUCUUAUAAUGCCAAUUUUAUUGGAGCUUUGUUGCAUUUAUUUUUGGCUCUAUGGUCCAUAAAUGGGAGUUAAUAGCAAACGUUUUAUUAAAAAUGUCUUAGCUUUCCCCCAAAUUAUAUCAUUUUUUAGAAGUUUUAUCCUUCUGGGGUGUUUUUGGCUUUCUGAGCUUUAAGAUAUUAAUGAAUUUUUUCCACAUACUUCAUGGGUUUGGUUUUAAGUAUGAGGUUAAAAUUGUGGAUUUUAAAAAGCUAAUAAAUACUUGAAGUGAAUAUAUAGAGAGAGCCAGAUUUCCCCAAAACUCUGUGAGCUGUGUGUGUUUUGUGUAGAAUAUUAGCCAUAAUUAACUUUUCCCUUUUUUUUUUUGGAGACAGGGUCUUACUCUGUCACCCAGGAUGGAGUGCAGUGGUGCGGUCUCAGCUCACUGCAGCCUCGACCUCCUGGGUUCAAGAGAUUCUCGUGCGUCAACCUCCCAAGUAGCUGGGAUUACAGAUGCCUGCCACCAUGCCCAGCUAAGUUUUGUAUUUUUUUUUUUGUUUGUUUUAGUAAAGAUGGGAUUUCACCAUGUUGGCCAGGCUGGUCUCAAACUCCUGCCCUCAAGUGAUCCCACCCACCUCAGACUCCCAAAGUGCUGGGAUUACAGGUGUGAGCCACCACUCCUGGGAAAUAAUUAACUUUUUCACAUAGAAAAUAGAUCACAGAUAAAAGCUCCUCACAUAUUUUGAAGGUCAAAAAAAAAUUUGCUGUUGCUAACAAUUGCCUUUGAACCAUGAAAGAGGAAAAACUAACUUUAUUUGAGCAACUUGUCAUUUGAGACUUAAACUAACUUAUCAAACUUAGCAGAAUUAACUUGUGAGUAUUGACUUAAGUGAAGUUAGUUUAUAUACUUUACUAUUCUGUCAUGCAAAUAAAAUGGCUUAGAGCAAGUUCAUACACAGUUACUUUUAUCUACAAAUGUAGAAAUCUUACCUAUUUGAAAUUUACAUUAUUCCCUGAAACUAUGCCUAUUGAGAGAGAGUUUAUAGAAGUAUUAUCUGAGAAACCUGAGUUUGAUUUUCUUUUUGUGACAUUCCUGUUAAUGUCACUUUUAAACAAGCCACUUAACCUAUGUCAUUUUCAGUUUCUUCUGUAAAAUGGCGAUAAUGAUACCUACCAGUAUUGUUACGAAGUUCAAAUAGGCCCUAUCCACAGCACUUAGUAGGUGUUAAAUGAAUGCGUCUUGUUACUUGAACAAGAAGUGGUUAGUUAUGAUAGUUUAUUUUUUUCUGACAAAUUUACUGUCUUUUAUAAAAAGAAAUAGCUAGGAUUUCCUGUGUUAUCCUGCCAUUUUUAUAAUCAAACAAAAUUAUUAAUAUUCUCCUUAGACUAAAUCAUUAAUUUAACAAAUCUCAAGCAUCUACUAUAUGCCAAGAAGUAUUCUAGGCCUGAAUAUAUUGCAGGGCACGAAGCAAGACAGUAAUUUCGAACCUUUAUGGGAUUUUUAUUUUAAUUGGUUAGUAAAAUAGUUUAUCAUUUGGUGACAAGGUUAUAUGGGGAAAGUAAGUUGAGGAAGGGGCCCAGAGAGUGUGUGAGGAUAGGAUUACUAUUAAGUAGCAUGUACACUGAUAUGUGACAUUGAGCAGAGGCCUGAGGAGGUGAAUGGUUGUGCAGUGUGGAUAUCUGGGAGGAGAGCAUUCCAGGCAGAAGGAAUAUUACAUGCUAAGGCCCUGAGCUGGUACAGAGUGUAAAGAAACAGUAAAGAGAUCAGUGUGACUGUAGUGAACAAUAAUAGCAUUUUAGGGAGAAUUAGAAAAUGAACUGAGAGAGAUUGGGAGUAAUAAUCCUGCCUGAUUGUAGGUAAUUACGUAGGGCAUUAUAGCCCUUUCUCAAGAGUAGGACUUUACUGAGUGAGCUAGCAAGCAAUUAGGAUUCAGAUCAAAGCAAGGAUGGAAGCAGGUAGUAGUAGGAAGAUAAUAUGGUAAAUCCAGGUGACAAAUGGUACAAUUUGAGAUUAAGAGUAAUGGAAAUAAUAAGUGGUCAGAUUCUGAAUGUAUUUUGGUGGUAGCACCAAAAGGAUAUGCUGAUAGAAUGGAUGUGAGGUAUGAAAAAAAGAAUGAUCAAGGUUUUUGGCUUGAAGAAUGAAGUGGGCAUUAAUAAGAUGGCGAAGACUCAGAGGAGCAGGCUUAAGCGGGUAGAUUGAGAGUUUACUUUUGGAUAUGUUAUGGUAGACUUGUCUGUCAGACGUCCAAAGGAAAAUGUAGAGUGGGCAGUUGGAUAUUUGAACCUGGAAAAGUAGAGGUCUGGGCUGGAGAUAAAUAUAUUUGGAAGUCAUCAGUGUGUAAUCUUAUUUUAAGUCAGGACAUGGAUGAAACCACUUAGAGAGUAAGUGUAGCCAGAGGAUAGAACUUAAUUGAAGACAUAUGAUCGAUGAAAUUCAAGGCCAACUUUUGUGAUUUUUCAAAUAGAAAUAAAAUGUUAACAUUUUCUACCACACAUAUACAAACCAUUACUUUCUAUAGUGUUGUAGAAGCACUAAGAUUUAAAAAGCAAGAUUGAUAAUAGUUGCCAAAUAUGUAAACAAAUGGCAAAUUAAAUUGAGGAGGGAGUGUCACUUUAUUCUUGGAAUAAAGUUUUUGUUUUGAAGUAAUACAGUUUUUUAUAUUAAGAAUAACAACAUCUGGAGUGCUAGUUUCUUUUUCUCAUUGUUGGAAAUUGCUAUUCCAAUUCAAUUUGACAGUUUUAGCACUAGAGGGCAGGCUUGCUUCUAGAUUGUGAAGAGUUCUACAUGAAUUAAUAUAGCCAAACAGCGCAGGUUGAACAUCCUUAACUUGAAAAUCUGAAAUUCAAAAUGCUUCAAAAUCCAAAACUUUUUGAGUGUUGACAUGAUGCCACAAGUGGAAAAUUCCACACCUGACCUCAUAUGAUGGGUCACAGUCAAAAUGCAGGUGUACAACAGUUUACUCUGUUCCCAAGAGAAAAAUAAAAUUAGCUGCAGGCUAUGUGUAAAAAGUGUAUAUGAAACAUAAAUGAAUUUCAUGUUUAGACUUGGGUCCCAUCCCCAAGGUAUCUUAUUAUGAAUAUGCAAAUAUUCAAAGAUCAAAAAAAAGAAAUCUAAAACACUUCCGGUCCCAAGCAUUUUGGAUAAGAGAUAUUCAACCUGCACCUACAUUCAAUCUCAAUUAAUGAAUGCAGUUGUUUCUUAUGUGACAGGUUUGCCAUCUACUAUGUUUUUUUCUAGUGCUAGGAAAGCAUAAAAUAAGGCUAAUUGAUUUUAGUACAUCUAGGACUGGCAGUUGACGCUAAUAUACAUUUGAAUAUAAAUGUAUAUUUAUAUUCCAAGGAGUUUCCAAGGAAACUCAAGUGUAGCUUAAUUAUACUCAGAUUUGAUAUAGAGGGUCUUCCACCACAUAUAUGAAUAUUAAAGCCAGUCAGAAGAAAUCCUGGACAUGAAAACAUUUUUUCAGGAAAUAAUUAACUAUGUGCUGGGUAUUAUUAUAUGAGCGUGGCUACAAAGAUGAAUAAAAUAUAGUCCCUGCCUAAAUAAGCUUUGUUGUAGCAUCUUACAGCACUUAAUAUCUUGUGCUGUAUCUAUUUAAAUGUCUUUUUCCCUUCAAUAAUAGAAAUCCUGACUCACUUAUUUUUGGUGCCUCCAAGUGCCCAUCACACAAUUCAGUUUACAGUGUUUGAACAUGUGAAUAAUGAGAGAGAGAAAAAUAAGAAAACGGUCAGGGAAUUGGGGCCUUUGAAAAAACUUAUUUUCACAUUUUUACCCUUAGAGAGAUGCUUUUCCUAUUAACACGUCUAAAGAUUAUGGAGACAAUUCUAACCUUCUAUCUUUGCUCCCACUACUUCUUCAAGCAGACUUUAACCCCAUUCCUCAAGAGCAGUUAUUGGCAGCCAUAGAGAGUGGGAGGUCAAGCCUUUUUUAGUCAUUGGAGUAAACAGGAGACAUAGAUGUGGAAAUUGGGAGGUUCUCUCUAUCUGGCUUACGUCAGUUUGAGAAGUUUGACAUGAAAUGGAACCUUCUGGAAUGAGGUUCUUUUUCCUGCUUUUCACCUGGAAAGUUUUCCCAUACAUGGUCCUCUUGCACCCCUAGUCCUUUUAGGGUACCUAUUUCUGUGUGCUAGUUCUUUCAUUUCCUUGUCUGUAACAUGAGGAUAAUAAUAGUCCUUAUCUAAUAGCAUUAUUUUGAGGAUGAAAUGAAAUACAGGCAGUAAAUAUUAGUUACUCUUUGCUAUCUGGAAAAACAUCAAUUGAACCUCAUAGGAUGGACUUGUGUUCAAUAAGUGUUAUAUAUAGUAGAGUCAAAUGGAAAAAUUGAACCACUCAGAUACAUUUUUUUCAUUGAUACAUAAUAGAUGUAUUUAUUUGGGGGGUACAUGUGAUAAUAUGAUAUAUUCAUAUAAUUAAAAUUCAUUGAUACAUGAUGUAUUUAUUUGGGGGUACAUGUGAUAGUAUGAUAUAUUCAUAUAAUUAAAAUUCAUUGAUACAUAAUGUAUUUAUUUGGGGGGUACAUGUGAUAGUAUGAUAUAUUCAUAUAAUUAAAUGAAGAUAAUUGGGAUAUCCAUCACCUUAAAUAUUUAUGUUUUCUUUACACUAGGAACAUUCGAAUUCUCUUUAGCUAUUUUGAAAUGUACAAUAGUUUAGUGUUAAUAGAUCAGUCAUCCUACUGAUAUAUCGAACACCAGGUCUUAUUUCUUCUGUCUACAUAGACAUAUUUAGAAAUGCAAAUCUCUUAGGAAAUUAAUCUGUAAUGUCAAUGAUGCACACUGAUUUGUAUUACUUGCUUUCUUUGUAGGCAGUAUAGUGAAAUGGUUCAUUAAAUGGAUGCUAAAUAUGACUAAAUGAUCAAUUUACAGUGUAGUUGGCACCAAGUAAUAAAUGCUCAGUAACAUAGCUACUAUGGCUGUCUUUAAAAGUGGAUUGGUUUGACUUCAUAGGAAGGACUCUAUUUUUAAAAAAGAGAAAUAUUAAAAAAUAAAAAGCCAAAAUUCUAUGAUGUCUUAUUACAUUGAGUCUCUUAAAUCAGUUUUUUUUUAAUUAAGUAGCAGGACCCUAUUGCAAAAUAAGUUUUACCUAGAAGCACAGUAUUUAAAACAGAAAGCUAAAAUACUCUGGUUAAGUGGGAAGCUCCCUGUCUUCCUCGCUGCUAGUAUUAUUUCUGAAAAACCUCAAAGGAACUCCUUGCUCUCUGAAUAGCAGGUUUUAAAAACCACUACUUGCACAUUUGCACCUUGACAUCAAACAUGUGAACAAAGUAAUAGAGUGAGAAAACUGAAUUUCUAUUUAGGAAUUUCUAUUUUAUUCUCUCUAUAAAAAGCCAAGAAGUGGUUGGUGUUUGGAAUAACAUGAAAAAUAUUCCAAGUAUCUUUGGAAAUACUUACACUAGAACUAUAAGGUUUAUGAUAAUUCUAUCUUAGAUUCAUUAUCUAGAGCUGGUCUAAAAAAGGAUGAUAUGUAAGAACUACCAAGAGAGACUUGGAGUAGAUACAAGAAUGAAGGAAUGAAUCAAUAUCCAAUAAAUAUCCAUAGGCCCAGGCUUUGCUAUGCCCUCUUAUUACACAGGAUAAAACAGUGUAGUUGUUAGUUUCUACCUUUGAAGAUUAUGAUCCUUAAAAAGGAAACAGCUCUGUGAACAGAGACCAUGUUAUUCAUAGGUGUUCCUCACUUGUUUCCACCACAUAAUAGGUAUUUAAUGAAUGAAAAAAUUCACGUCUCUCUUUGAUCCUAGACUGCAAGUUACUUAAAAGAAAUGGACCGUAUUUUACUUAUCUCUCAUGGCCUGCAAAUUGAGUUUGCUUACUGAAUUAAUGAAUGAAUGACCAAUUGUACACAUAUGUCUGUAAAACGUUUACAUAUCCACAUUCCCAUUAGACUGAGAUUCUUGAGGGCAGAAACCAUGUCUUCAGCUCUCAGCAUGGUGCCUGACUCAUGGUAGGUUGUCAAAAGCAUUUGCAGAACUGAAUAAAACUUACGUUUAAGUAGUACUGGAGCAGUCUCACAUAACCGGGCACAGUGUCUUCUAAAUAGACACUAAAAUUAUUUCAUAAUUAAAGACAGAUCUCACUAAGCAUUUUCUGAGUUAGUGCCAGUUGAAUAAUAUGACAAUAAGCUAUAGGAGUUCAGAGGAGAGUGAGUUCUGUGGACUGAAAUAGUCAAAGUGGAUUUUCAGAGCAGAUGAGACGCGAUGAAGGCUGGGGCUACUUUGGUGUUUUAAGAACAUUAAUUAGGCAGCAGGAAAAUCUGAGGACAGGGAGACUAGUAAGGAAGGCUGGAAAGAGCCCUGGGUUUGGAGUUCAGAGAUCUGUGUUCAGAGUCCUUUGCUUCUUAGUGACUAUGUGACCUUGAGAAGAUAACUUGAGCUCCCUUUUUCCUCUUCUGUGAGGUAGAGGUAAGAUUGAUGUGCAUAUUGAUAUUGUACUUAAAAGUGUUUGUAAAAUGCUAAGUAAAACCUAAUGCUAUGCUUUGAAUGUAGUGGGUUCCAAAUAUUUGUUUAAUGACAAAGAAUAAAUGAUAUUGACUAAUGAAAAUAAUGGAGCCACUGGAAUGUCACCUCCUGCAUCUGCCAGUAAACCUGUUAACACAGGGGUGGCGGGGGGGGGGGGGAAGUAAAUAUGUGAAGCCACCAAAUCUCAUGAUCAGGAGAAAAACUUUGGAACUCCCAUGAGACUCCAAAGUUAUGUCACAGGUGAAUAAGUCAUGAACUUUUCAUGCUGAUAUCAUUUCUAAGGUUGCUGCCUUGUCAGAAGAAGCAAACCACAAGAUAAACCAUGCAGAAAAUCUUUUUUUAAAAAAGUUUCCUGAAGGAUGGAUGGUUCAUUUGUUCUGCUUGUCACUUUACUUACUAAUGAGUCAUUUUUUUCCUUAACCAGUAAUUUGUUUUAAAUUUGGUCAUAAGAUGGUAUGUUGACUAGUCCAAUGUUACAAAAUAAUUGGAAAAAAGAUGACAGACCACCAACUGAAUAAGGGAAAUCUGGUUCUUGAACUUCCAAUGUAUGAAUUGGUGAUGGUAAGCUUAGUCUUUAUGAUGUAAGAUUGGAUUUAUUGGAACUUCUUUAUGUCCAGAAGUUGCAGCACCUUUCUUUGUCUCUGGAAUGCCCAAGAUCUCUACUGCAUCCUGUAGACAUGGAGGGUUUCCCCCCUUAUUCUGGGUCUGAUUAUUUUUAAAGAAACACCCUUUCCUUACCCAUCAUGGAGACACUACUAACCUUGUAUAUACUUUUAUUAGAGUGCUGAUAACACCAUAUUACAGUAGCAUACUUACAUAUCUGUUUUCUUAACUGUGAGCUCCUUGAGAGCAGGGACUGUGUGUUUUUGCUUUUAUUUCACCAGUACUCAGAACUAUCCACAGUAUAGAAAAGCACUCAAUAAAUGGAAUAAAUGAAAAUGAAUAGAUAAAUAAAUGAUUUCACUUGUAUAAGA